AGUUACUGUUUGAUUCAAAGAGUCUUAAAGACAGGUCUCCGUAUUAGACCUUGUAAUACGCUUACCUAGAUCUGAGAAGGACUUUCAGGAUAGAACAUGAUUCCAUGUGGAUGGCUCAUGAACAAAAAUGAGAAACACGACGAUAAACUGGUAAUGUUCACCAAUCAAUCUGAAGAUUCUGAAAGAUGUGAAAGCAUGGAGCUGGACAAAAAAAUCCAGGAUCUGAUUGAGAGAAAUGCGUCUCCUCAUCCAAAACGGUUCACCCCAGAGGCCAUGCCAACUCACAGAAAUCUAUGUUCUCUGAAGCCACUUCCUGUUACUAAAGAAAUUCUUCAGCAGAAGAAUUUGCUGGCACUUUCCACUUUAAAGUGUCCAGGCAGCUGUGACUACAAGAAGACUCCAGGAAAAACAGCUUCCAUGGCACAUUUUGUACAGGGCACAUCUAGAAUGAUUGCCGCAGAAAGUUCUACGGAGCAUAAAGAGUGUGCUGAACCAUCAACAAGAAAGAACUUGAUGAAUUCUCUUGAACAAAAGAUAAGGUGUUUGGAAAAACAAAGAAAAGAGCUCCUGGAAGUUAACCAGCAAUGGGAUCAGCAAUUUAGAAGUAUGAAAGAGUUAUAUGAAAGAAAGGUAGCAGAGCUGAAGACGAAACUGGACGCCGCGGAAAGAUUCCUCAGCACGCGGGAGAAGGAUCCGCAUCAGAGGCAGAGAAAGGACGACAGGCAGAGAGAGGACGACAGGCAGCGCGACCUGACCCGGGACCGGCUGCAGCGGGAGGAGAAGGAAAAGGAACGCCUAAAUGAAGAAUUACAUGAAUUGAAAGAAGAGAAUAAACUUUUAAAGGGAAAAAAUACUCUUGCGAACAAGGAAAAGGAACAUUACGAAUGUGAAAUAAAACGCCUCAAUAAGGCUCUUCAGGAUGCCUUGAAUAUCAAGUGUUCAUUUUCCGAGGACUGUUUGAGGAAGUCUCGAGUGGAAUUCUGCCAUGAGGAGAUGAGAACAGAAAUGGAAGUUCUGAAGCAGCAGGUGCAAAUAUACGAAGAAGACUUCAAAAAGGAACGAUCGGAUCGAGAGAGACUUAAUCAAGAGAAAGAGGAGCUACAGCAAAUUAAUGAAACUUCCCAAUCCCAGUUGAACAGGCUGAAUUCCCAGAUAAAAGCUUGUCAGAUGGAGAAAGAAAAACUAGAAAAGCAAUUAAAACAGAUGUAUUGCCCACCCUGUAACUGCGGCUUGGUUUUCCACCUGCAAGAUCCAUGGGUACCAACAGGCCCUGGAGCUGUGCAGAAGCAACGGGAGCACCCACCAGACUAUCAGUGGUAUGCUCUUGACCAGCUUCCGCCAGAUGUACAACACAAGGCAAAUGGUUUAUCCUCAGUAAAGAAAGUCCAUCCGUAGAAGUACACACUAACAGAGAGAGACAACAGGCAACGAGGGAGCGUGGCUGAGGACCCUCUUCUUUGUUUAUACUGAGGCUUGUUUCUGCCACAAAGGCACAUCAUCUACCCUGUUAUUUGUGCCUGGUCAUGUUUUCCUUUGGUAUGAAUACAGGAAAAGGCUUCUGACAGCUAAGAUCCUGAUCAAAUUGGAGGAGCCAGUUAUUAUACAACCAAAUACAACUUCCAGUUUCCUUGAAAUGAGACUUGGCAGAUGGAUGAUGCACGACUCCCUGAAAAUCUCUUCAGCAUAUUGCUGUUGGAUGCACAAAAAUGAUUCUAUGAUUUAGGCAACUCAGUGUUUGCUGCAGGGAUAUUGUAUGUUGAUUUAAAGUGCAUAUGUGUGUGUGUGUGUGUGUGUGUGUGUGUGUGUGUGUGUUUCCUGGGGUAAAAAUUUCUGCAGUUGUAAACGUUUAACAUUGCUCCCAUUCUUCUUCCACAGGGCCUUAGUUCUUUAGCUAUUUGACUACAUAUUGUUGACCUCAGUGAUCCUAAACGUAGAAUUGAAGAGGUGUAUAUACCUCAUUAAAUUAAAUAAGUGGUUCAAUCUGAAUAAGAUGGUUAAUUGGAAGCUAUUCCUUAGACAGAUCAUUUCUUUAAGAUGAUGAGAAAUUGUGCGCCUGCAUCACAAGACUUGAUUAUGAAAGAUAAAGUCUUGGGCUGGGUGCAGUGGCUCAUGCCUAUAAUCCCAGCACUUUGGGAGGCUGAGGCAGGUGGAUUGCUUUGAGGCCAGGAGUUCUAGACCAGCCUGGCCAGCAUGGUGAAACCCCAUCUCUACUAUAAAUACAAAAAUUAGCCAGGCUCGUGGCACACACCUAUAAACCCAGCUACUCAGGAGGCUUGAGGCGGGAGGAUCACUUGAGCCCAGGGAGGCAGAGGUUGCUGUAAGUUGAGAUCGCCACUGCACUCCAGCCUGGGAAAUAGAGUGAGCAAGACUCAGUGCCCCCUACCCACCCACUCCACACCACCAAAAAAAAAAAAAAAAAAAAAAGGAAGACAAAGUCCUGAUGGGAUGAUGAUGGCUAUAUGGCUAUGCUGUGUCCAUAUAUACUUACAGAAAUAUUUCAGACAUAUGGAUUUAUAGUUAAAUCUGUGUUUUUCCUUCCCUUGGAUUUGAUUAAUUUUAAUGAAAAACUUAAUUCUGACUUCUCAAGCCAAUUAAAAUGAAAAUGGAAUUUAUUGAAA